AUGGAGGUCUCGGGGCACCCCCAGGCCAGGAGAUGCUGCCCAGAGGCCCUGGGAAAGCUCUUCCCUGGCCUCUGCUUCCUCUGCUUUCUGGUGACCUACGCCCUGGUGGGUGCUGUGGUCUUCUCUGCCAUUGAGGACGGCCAGGUCCUGGUGGCAGCAGAUGAUGGAGAGUUUGAGAAGUUCUUGGAGGAGCUCUGCAGAAUCUUGAACUGCAGUGAAACAGUGGUGGAAGACAGAAAACAGGAUCUCCAGGGGCAUCUGCAGAAGGUGAAGCCUCAGUGGUUUAACAGGACCACACACUGGUCCUUCCUGAGCUCGCUCUUUUUCUGCUGCACGGUGUUCAGCACCGUGGGCUAUGGCUACAUCUACCCCGUCACCAGGCUUGGCAAGUACUUGUGCAUGCUCUAUGCUCUCUUUGGUAUCCCCCUGAUGUUCCUCGUUCUCACGGACACAGGCGACAUCCUGGCAACCAUCUUAUCUACAUCUUAUAAUCGGUUCCGAAAAUUCCCUUUCUUUACCCGCCCCCUCCUCUCCAAGUGGUGCCCCAAAUCUCUCUUCAAGAAAAAACCGGACCCCAAGCCCGCAGAUGAAGCUGUCCCUCAGAUCAUCAUCAGUGCUGAAGAGCUUCCAGGCCCCAAACUUGGCACAUGUCCUUCACGCCCAAGCUGCAGCAUGGAGCUGUUUGAGAGAUCUCAUGCGCUAGAGAAACAGAACACACUGCAACUGCCCCCACAAGCCAUGGAGAGGAGUAACUCGUGUCCCGAACUGGUGUUGGGAAGACUCUCAUACUCCAUCAUCAGCAACCUGGAUGAAGUUGGACAGCAGGUGGAGAGGUUGGACAUCCCCCUCCCCAUCAUUGCCCUUAUUGUUUUUGCCUACAUUUCCUGUGCAGCUGCCAUCCUCCCCUUCUGGGAGACACAGUUGGAUUUCGAGAAUGCCUUCUAUUUCUGCUUUGUCACACUCACCACCAUUGGGUUUGGGGAUACUGUUUUAGAACACCCUAACUUCUUCCUGUUCUUCUCCAUUUAUAUCAUCGUUGGAAUGGAGAUUGUGUUCAUUGCUUUCAAGUUGGUGCAAAACAGGCUGAUUGACAUAUACAAAAAUGUUAUGCUAUUCUUUGCAAAAGGGAAGUUUUACCACCUUGUUAAAAAGUGA